AUGCAGAAACACUCUCCAGGCCCCCCAGCCCUGGCCCUCCUCUCUCAGUCUCUGCUCACUACAGGAAAUGGCGACACUUUGAUUAUCAAUUGCCCAGGCUUUGGCCAGCACAGGGUGGACCCUGCAGCCUUUCAAGCAGUGUUUGACAGAAAGGCUAUUGGUCCAGUCACCAACUACAGUGUCGCCACUCAUGUCAACAUCUCCUUCACCUUGUCUGCCAUCUGGAACUGCUAUUCCAGGAUUCACACCUUCAACUGCCACCAUGCCCGGCCUUGGCACAAUCAAUUUGUGCAGUGGAACCCAGAUGAAUGCGGAGGCAUCAAGAAGUCCGGCAUGGCAACUGAGAACCUAUGGCUUUCAGAUGUCUUCAUCGAGGAGUCUGUGGAUCAGACACCUGCAGGUCUCAUGGCUAGUAUGUCAAUAGUGAAGGCCACAUCAAACACAAUAAGCCAAUGUGGGUGGUCAGCAUCUGCAAACUGGACACCUUCUAUUUCCCCUUCCAUGGACAGAGCCCGGGCAUGGAGAAGGAUGUCCAGGAGCUUUCAAAUACAUCACAGAACCUCAUUCAGAACAAGGAGGGAGUGGGUACUGCUGGGUAUCCAAAAAAGAACAAUAAAGGUGACCGUGGCCACUAACCAGUAUGAACAAGCCAUCUUCCAUGUGGCCAUCAGGCGCAGGUGCAGGCCCAGCCCCUACGUGGUAAACUUUCUGGUGCCCAGUGGCAUUCUGAUUGCCAUCGAUGCCCUCAGUUUCUACCUGCCACUGGAAAGUGGGAAUUGUGCCCCAUUCAAGAUGACUGUUCUGCUGGGCUACAGCGUCUUCCUGCUCAUGAUGAAUGACUUGCUCCCAGCCACUAGCACUUCAUCACAUGCUUCACUAGUGGCGCCUCUGGCCCUCAUGCAGACCCCCUUGCCUGCAGGUGUCUACUUCGCCCUGUGCCUGUCCCUGAUGGUGGGCAGCCUGCUGGAGACCAUCUUCAUCACCCACCUGCUGCACGUGGCCACCACCCAGCCCCUACCUCUGCCUCGGUGGCUCCACUCCCUGCUGCUGCACUGCACCGGCCAAGGGAGAUGCUGUCCCACUGCGCCCCAGAAGGGAAAUAAGGGCCCGGGUCUCACCCCCACCCACCUGCCCGGUGUGAAGGAGCCAGAGGUAUCAGCAGGGCAGAUGCCAGGCCCUGGGGAGGCAGAGCUGACAGGGGGCUCAGAAUGGACAAGGGCCCAGCGGGAACACGAGGCCCAGAAGCAGCACUCGGUGGAGCUGUGGGUGCAGUUCAGCCACGCGAUGGACGCCCUGCUCUUCCGCCUCUACCUGCUCUUCAUGGCCUCCUCCAUCAUCACCGUCAUAUGCCUCUGGAACACCUAGGCAGGUGCUCACCUGCAAACUUCAGUCUGGACUUCUUUUUGCCAGAGAACUCCAGAAACCAGUCAGGCUCUCAGUCAGCCUUGUGGCCCUGUCAACCGCCUCAUUUUUAACCCAGUCCUCUGUGUAGUUUCAGACCAGACCUGAAUAGUCUCCUAUGCCCUCCAAAAGUCGGGUCCUUGCUCCUGCAUGCCAUCAGCCCCACUCAGCCCUCCCAUACCUCCCUGGCUCCUCAGGAUUCAGGUUCCUAGGGUACGUCCUUGAUUAAAUCACCCCAAUAUGCCCCUUUGCAGAAAGUAUUGGCUUUUCCCUGAAUUCUGUUAUGGUAAAAAAAAUCUUGGGAUUGAGAGUCUUCUUGCAGAAACUUCUCAGCCAAAGUAAAAAGGAUUUUCUCUUA